GAGCGCGCGUGGCCCCGGAGCCGCCGGCGCCGCGCGGGGAAUAGCUGUGCAGCACGCCGAGCCCGGACUCGGCUGGCUCGGCUCGGCGCGGGCGGGCGAGAGGAUGCUGGCGGGCUUCCCCGGGCUCGGCCCGCGCUCCCGCCGGGGAGGGCCCCGCGCGCGCCCCUAGCAGCCGCCGCCGCCGCGGGUGCAGGGGAGGGGUCCGGAGAGCCGCGCUCGCCGCCGCCCGCGCCUGCCGGCCCCCGCACGGCCCCUGCCCCUGAGCCUCAGCCCCAGGGCGGGCGCGCUGGGCCGGCGCCCACGGAUCUCCCAGCCCUCGUCGCCGCCUCCUCCUUCCCCCUGCGGCCGGGCGCCCGCGGAUGCUGAGGGGCAGCCCUGCGCCUCUCCCGGUCGGAUCCCGGGCCUGACGGCGGGAGAUCGCGCUCCGGCCGGGCCCCGAGGCGCUGCCGGGGCGGCGCGGCUCUGCGGGGAGCAGCCCUCGGGCGCGCCGAGCUCUCCCGCCCCAGCCCGCGCGGGGACCGUCCCGGAGCACGCGGUGGCCGAGUUCCCGCACAGUUCUAGCUGAUCAGUGCUACCUGUGCUCUGGAAACCCGCUCUGCGUUCCUGCUGGAGGUGGCCUCCCCUCCGCCCCAGACAAGAAGAGGCCCUCAGCCCUCCCCCGGUCUCAGAGAGCCCUGAGAGGAGGCCCAGUCCAGAGCUCUUCCUCCGUUCCCAGUCCACUUCUCUAGGGCCAGUAGCAGACACCAGCCAGUAUGCCGAGGAACCAGGGCUUCUCCGAGCCCGAAUACUCGGCCGAGUACUCAGCCGAGUACUCCGUCAGCCUGCCCUCCGACCCUGACCGCGGGGUGGGCCGGACCCAUGAAAUCUCGGUCCGGAACUCGGGCUCCUGCCUGUGCCUGCCUCGCUUCAUGCGGCUGACUUUCGUGCCGGAGUCCUUGGAGAACCUCUACCAGACCUACUUCAAAAGGCAGCGCCACGAGACCCUGCUGGUGCUGGUGGUCUUUGCAGCCCUCUUUGACUGCUACGUGGUGGUCAUGUGUGCUGUGGUCUUCUCCAGCGACAAGCUGGCUUCCCUCGCCGUGGCUGGAAUUGGACUGGUGUUGGACAUCAUCCUCUUCGUGCUCUGCAAAAAGGGGCUGCUCCCGGACCGGGUCACCCGCAGAGUGCUGCCCUACGUGCUGUGGCUGCUCAUAACCGCCCAGAUCUUCUCCUACCUGGGCCUGAACUUCGCGCGUGCCCACGCGGCUAGUGACACGGUGGGCUGGCAGGUCUUCUUUGUCUUCUCCUUCUUCAUCACGCUGCCCCUCAGCCUCAGCCCCAUCGUGAUCAUCUCCGUGGUCUCCUGUGUGGUGCACACGUUGGUCCUGGGGGUCACCGUGGCCCAGCAGCAGCAGGAGGAGCUCAAGGGGAUGCAGCUGCUGCGGGAGAUCCUGGCCAACGUCUUCCUCUACCUGUGCGCCAUCGCUGUGGGCAUCAUGUCCUACUACAUGGCUGACCGCAAGCACCGCAAGGCCUUCCUGGAGGCCCGCCAGUCGCUGGAGGUGAAGAUGAACCUGGAAGAGCAGAGCCAGCAGCAGGAGAACCUCAUGCUUUCCAUCCUGCCCAAGCACGUGGCUGACGAGAUGCUGAAAGACAUGAAGAAAGACGAGAGCCAGAAGGACCAGCAGCAGUUCAACACCAUGUACAUGUACCGUCACGAGAACGUCAGCAUCCUCUUUGCCGACAUCGUGGGCUUUACCCAGCUGUCUUCUGCCUGCAGUGCCCAGGAGCUUGUGAAGCUGCUCAACGAGCUCUUUGCCCGCUUUGACAAGCUGGCAGCUAAAUACCACCAGCUGCGGAUUAAGAUCCUGGGCGACUGCUACUACUGCAUCUGCGGCUUGCCCGACUACCGGGAGGACCACGCCGUCUGCUCCAUCCUCAUGGGGCUGGCCAUGGUGGAGGCCAUCUCGUAUGUGCGGGAGAAGACCAAGACUGGGGUGGACAUGCGUGUGGGGGUGCACACGGGCACCGUGCUGGGGGGCGUCCUGGGCCAGAAGCGCUGGCAGUACGACGUGUGGUCGACUGAUGUCACUGUAGCCAACAAGAUGGAGGCCGGCGGCAUCCCUGGGCGCGUGCACAUCUCCCAGAGCACCAUGGACUGCCUGAAAGGGGAGUUUGAUGUGGAGCCAGGCGAUGGGGGCAGCCGCUGUGAUUACCUAGAAGAGAAGGGUAUUGAAACCUACCUCAUCAUUGCCUCCAAGCCAGAGGUGAAGAAAACAGCCACCCAGAAUGGCCUCAAUGGCUCGGCCCUGCCCAAUGGAGCACCAGCUUCCUCAAAGUCCAGCUCCCCUGCCCUCAUUGAGACCAAGGAGCCCAACGGGAGUGCCCACAGCAGUGGGUCCACGUCGGAGAAGCCCGAGGAGCAGGAUGCCCAGGCCGACAACCCCUCAUUCCCCAACCCACGCCGGAGGCUGCGCCUGCAGGACCUGGCUGACCGAGUGGUGGAUGCCUCUGAAGAUGAGCACGAGCUCAACCAGCUGCUCAACGAGGCCCUGCUUGAGCGAGAGUCCGCCCAAGUAGUAAAGAAGAGAAACACCUUCCUCUUGUCCAUGCGGUUCAUGGACCCCGAGAUGGAAACCCGCUACUCGGUGGAGAAGGAGAAGCAGAGUGGGGCUGCCUUCAGCUGCUCCUGCGUCGUCCUGCUCUGCACGGCCCUGGUCGAGAUACUCAUCGACCCCUGGCUAAUGACAAACUAUGUGACCUUCAUGGUGGGGGAGAUUCUGCUCCUCAUCCUGACCAUCUGCUCCCUGGCUGCCAUCUUUCCCCGGGCCUUUCCUAAGAAGCUUGUGGCCUUCUCAACUUGGAUUGACCGGACCCGCUGGGCCAGGAACACCUGGGCCAUGCUCGCCAUCUUCAUCCUGGUGAUGGCAAAUGUCGUGGACAUGGUCAGCCACAUGGUGAAGCUCACGCUCAUGCUGCUCGUCGCAGGCGCCGUGGCCACCAUCAACCUCUAUGCCUGGCGUCCCGUCUUUGAUGAAUACGACCACAAGCGUUUUCGGGAGCACGACUUACCUAUGGUGGCCUUAGAGCAGAUGCAAGGAUUCAACCCUGGGCUCAAUGGCACUGACAGCAGGCUGCCCCUGGUGCCUUCCAAGUACUCUAUGACGGUGAUGGUGUUCCUCAUGAUGCUCAGCUUCUACUACUUCUCCCGCCACGUAGAAAAACUGGCACGGACACUUUUCUUGUGGAAGAUUGAGGUCCACGACCAGAAGGAACGUGUCUAUGAGAUGCGACGCUGGAACGAGGCCUUGGUCACCAACAUGUUGCCUGAGCACGUGGCACGCCAUUUCCUGGGGUCCAAGAAGAGAGAUGAGGAGCUGUAUAGCCAGACGUAUGAUGAGAUUGGAGUCAUGUUUGCCUCCCUGCCCAACUUUGCUGACUUCUACACAGAGGAGAGCAUCAACAAUGGUGGUAUUGAGUGUCUGCGUUUCCUCAAUGAAAUCAUCUCAGAUUUUGACUCUCUCCUGGACAAUCCCAAGUUCCGGGUGAUCACCAAGAUCAAAACCAUUGGCAGCACGUAUAUGGCGGCUUCAGGAGUCACCCCCGAUGUCAACACCAAUGGCUUUGCCAGCUCCAACAAGGAAGACAAGUCCGAGAGAGAGCGCUGGCAGCACCUGGCUGACCUGGCCGACUUCGCGCUGGCCAUGAAGGAUACGCUCACCAACAUCAACAACCAGUCCUUCAAUAACUUCAUGCUGCGCAUAGGCAUGAACAAAGGCGGGGUUCUGGCUGGGGUCAUCGGAGCCCGGAAACCACACUACGACAUCUGGGGCAAUACAGUCAAUGUAGCCAGCAGGAUGGAGUCCACGGGGGUCAUGGGCAACAUUCAGGUAUGUCCAGUGGCACAGCUGGCACGUGCUCAGACUCGGCAUGAGAACAAAACCGGAACAGUGCUUUCCCACGUGCCCCUGCCUCCCACCCUGGCCCUGAACAGUAAGUCCAGAGGCAGAGACGUGGGGCAAGUGGAAAAGAAUCUCUGCAAUAGCUAGCCUCAGCACAGGAAGAAACACUUCCACCCAUCCACAAAAUCUGGGCUGAAGUUCUAGAUGCAUAUGGCCUACCUUUGGGUAUGAACCUUCUAAUACCUUGUGAUCUGUCUCAGUGGCGUCUGGCAGAAAAGCUCCACGAAAGGGGCAAAGGGACAGAAGAGCAGGCAGUGGCAGUUUCCAGGUAACAGUGCUGCCACCCAGGUGACCAUGGCCAUCCUAGGAGAGAAGUCUCUGGAUGAGAGGAGGCCCCCAGCCAGUCACUCCAGGGUUCUCCUUCCCACCCGCUGCUCGCCACGGGUGGAAGGGCUUGGCCCUGGGAGGUUUGGGGAGUGUCCCGUACUGCUUGGGACCCAUGGAUCAGUGCUCGGCUCCAACCACCCAAAGCCCCCACCCGCCCUCAGUCUAGGCUCCCCCCGUAACGCCACGUUCUUGCUCCCCCUCCCUCUCCAGGUGGUAGAAGAAACCCAAGUCAUCCUCCGAGAGUACGGCUUCCGCUUUGUGAGGCGAGGCCCCAUCUUUGUGAAGGGGAAGGGGGAGCUGCUGACCUUCUUCUUGAAGGGGCGGGAUAAGCUAGCCACCUUCCCCAAUGGCCCCUCUGUCACACUGCCCCACCAGGUGGUGGACAACUCCUGAAUGGCCUCGAGCCUGCAACAGUCCAAACCGGAAGGGAGAAUUUAUUUUUUGAAACUGAAGGAAGUCCCGACCUUCCUGGAUUGAAGUGCACACUCAUGGACUUUAGGUUUAGAAACCUCCUCAGCCUUCAUUUGUUCGUGGAUGUGUGAGCUCUGAGGGUGGCCCUGCUAUUCCUGUGUGUGCCUGUAGUGUCCCCAGCAUAGGGGUCUUAGGCAUAGGGCUGAACAGUCCUUCCAGAGCCCUCGUUCCAAUCCCUGCCGUCCUUGCCCCUGAGGGGCCCUGACCACUGUGAGCAGGAGGGUGGCAGAGCUGGGACAAAGCUGCCUUUGCCGCUGGGCUUUCCGGGACUGUGGAGGGAGCACAGGCGGGGAAGCUCCACUUCAGACAGGGCUUGGUGGGGCAGGACAUGGCUCCCAUUUUGAAGGGAGGUCUCCAUGUGGUCCGAGUGAGGUGAGACGGCCCUCGUCCUGGUGUUCCUGAUCAUCUUGAAAGGUUCUUCUGGAACUCCUGUCCCCUUAGUCAUGAGAACAGAAAGUGCAAUAUUUCCUUUCACCUGGCAGGGGAGGGGGGAUUUAUUUCUGAAAGAAAAAUAUAUAAACAGAUCUUCUACAUUUAUAUUUUUAAUCUUCUGUUAAAUACACUUUCCGAUAUUGCCUUGCCUUUUGAGCUCUUGCUACAGUCGCCUUUGCUACUGCUUUAAGAGAAUUUACAGGUAUUGAUAAAGAACAAGACUGUUUUAUUAAAAGCUUUAUUCAACUUGAAA